GAAGAACUUAGGCUCCGGAGGCAGAGCCAAAGGCUGAAGGGGACUACUCCCUAGGACAGAGGCCGGGAGGUAUCGGGCCGACGAAGCCGAGUGGCGCGGAGGAGCGGAGCCUUCAGCCCCGCGGCUGGGCCGAGCCCGAAGGUGGCGUCGGUGUCGGGGAGCCGCCGCGUGCACCGGCCGUCCUCCCUGGGCCGCAUCGCGGUGGUGGUGGACCAGGGCUCGGGCUUCACCAAGGCGGGCUUCGCGGGCGAGAACCAGCCGCGCAUAGUGCUGAAGAGCUCUAGCUUGGUGCCCAGCUGGGACCGGCCGGUGCUGCCCGGAGCGCCGGGCUGCGAGCUGGCGGGCGGCGUGGCGCGGGCGCACCCCAUCAAGCACGGCGUGGUGGCGGACUGGGAGGCGCUGGAAGGGCUGUGGGAGCGCCUGCUGGUGGGCGGCCUGCGGGUGUGCCCAGAGCAGUGGCCCGUGCUGGUGAGCGACUCGCCGUUGGCGCCGCCCGCGGGCCGCGAAAGGGUGGCGGAGCUGCUGUUCGAGACCCUGGCAGUGCCCGCGUGCCACAUGGCUAGCACCGCGUUGCUGGCGCUCUGCUCCACCGGCGCGUUCAGCGGGCUGGCCGUGGAGGCGGGCGCGGGCGUGUGCCACGCCACGCCCAUCUACGCGGGUCACUCGUGGCACCAGGCCACCUUCCGACUGAACGUGGCAGGCAGCACCCUGUCGCGCUACCUGCGGGAUCUGCUGGUGGCGGCGAACCCUGACCUCUUGCAGCAGGCCCUGCCCCGCAAGGCCAUCACACAUCUCAAGAAGCGCAGCUGCUACGUGUCCCUGGACUUCGAGGGCGACCUCCGCGACCCCGCCCGCCACCAUCCGGCCAGUUUCAGCGUGGGUAACGGGUGCUGCGUCUGCCUCAGCAGUGAGCGCUUCCGCUGCCCCGAACCCAUCUUCCAGCCGGGCCUGCUGGGCCAGGCUGAGCAGGGGCUGCCCGCGCUGGCCUUCCGGGCGCUGCAGAAGAUGCCCAAAACGCUGCGGACACGCCUGGCAGACACCGUGGUGCUAGCCGGCGGCUCCACACUGUUUCCUGGCUUCGCCGAGCGCCUGGACAAGGAGCUGGAGGCGCAGUGCCGGCGGCACGGCUACGCGGCCCUGCGGCCCCACCUGGUGGCCAAGCAUGGGCGUGGCAUGGCUGUGUGGACCGGCGGCUCCAUGGUGGCCUCCCUGCACUCCUUCCAGCGCCGCUGGAUAACUCGGGCCAUGUACCAGGAGUGUGGCUCCAGGCUGCUGUACGAUGUGUUCAACUGAGUCAGGCUGGACUGGGGGGGGUGGCACUGCGUUGGGGGACAGCUCUCUAUCUAAAGAGUCAAGUGUUUGGAGCUGGCAGGGUCCUCCUGGAGGUUGGAGCUGACUGGAUGGGUCACCCCCAUACCCUUUCUGGGCCAGGAGAAGGUAUUUGGGACCCAUGGGACCCUCAUUUUGAACUGCAGUUUGAAUCUCCCCAACCACUGCCAGUUCAGAGAAUGCCAGUCCAGCUGCCUACCCACAGGGCCCUACUUUAUGGCAAUAAAGGUGAUGCCCCACUUGUGUCCAUGCCA